UAGUUCUGACUUGUUUAUCAUGUCUGUUCGGGGCAAGGCCGGAAAAGGCCUUGGGAAAGGCGGUGCCAAGUGCCAUCGCAAGGUACUGAGCGAUAAUAUUCAGGGCAUUACCAAGUGCACUAUCCGGCGCUUGGCCCGGCAUGGCGGUGUCAAGCGCAUCUUGGGCCUCAUUUAUGAGGAGACCCGCCGGGUGUUCAAGGUGUUCCUGGAAAAUGUGAUCUGGUACGCCGUGACCAACACGGAGCACGCCAAGCGCAAGACGGUCACCGCCAUGGCCGUGGUCUACGUGCUCAAACGCCAGGGAAGAACCCUGUAAGGCUUUGGCGGUUAAGUGAGGCCAGGCCUUUCCUUGCAAUAUCGUUAAUGGCCCUUUUCAGGGCCGCGUA